AGACGGCCAUUUGUGGCGGCGCUGGAGGCUGCGUUCGGCAGGCGCUGCGGAGACGCGUAGAGGAGCGCGCCCCCCGGCCGCUGCCGCCCCUGGCCCGUGCCGUCACCCCGCUUCUCCGCGCCUCGGGCGGUACCCAGCCAGUCCCCAGCGCCGCGCUACCGCGCUGACCGGCCCUCCAGACGCCUCCCGGUACCCGGGACCCCAGCCCGGCCGCUCGCCCGCAGCCCGCCGGCCGCACACGUCCCCGGAGCCGGGCCUAGGGCGGGCGGCAGCGGCGGCUCGGCGCAGUCAGGCUGGGCUCUGUAGCGUCCCCAUGGCCGCGGCCGGCUGGCGGGACGGCUCCGGCCAGGAGAAGUACCGGCUCGUGGUGGUCGGCGGGGGCGGCGUGGGCAAGUCGGCGCUCACCAUCCAGUUCAUCCAGUCCUAUUUUGUAACGGAUUAUGAUCCAACCAUUGAAGAUUCUUACACAAAGCAGUGUGUGAUAGAUGACAGAGCAGCCCGGCUAGAUAUUUUGGAUACAGCAGGACAAGAAGAGUUUGGAGCCAUGAGAGAACAGUAUAUGAGGACUGGCGAAGGCUUCCUGUUGGUCUUUUCAGUCACAGAUAGAGGCAGUUUUGAAGAAAUCUAUAAGUUUCAAAGACAGAUUCUCAGAGUAAAGGAUCGUGAUGAGUUCCCAAUGAUUUUAAUUGGUAAUAAAGCAGAUCUGGAUCAUCAAAGACAGGUAACACAGGAAGAAGGACAACAGUUAGCACGGCAGCUUAAGGUAACAUACAUGGAGGCAUCAGCAAAGAUUAGGAUGAAUGUAGAUCAAGCUUUCCAUGAACUUGUCCGGGUUAUCAGGAAAUUUCAAGAGCAGGAAUGUCCUCCUUCACCAGAACCAACACGGAAAGAAAAAGACAAGAAAGGCUGCCAUUGUGUCAUUUUCUAGAAUCCCUUCAGUUUUAGCUACCAACGGCCAGGAAAAGCCCUCAUCUUCUCUUUCUCUCCUCAGUUUACAUCUUGUUGGUACCUUUCUAGCCUUAGACAAAUGAUCACCAUGUUAGCCUUAGACGAAGAAGCUGGCUAGUCCUUUCUGUGAAGCUAAUACAAUGGUCAUUUCCAGACAAAUUUAAAGGAAACACUAAGGCUGCUUCAAAGAUUAUCUGAUUCCUUUAAAAUAUAUGUCUAUAUACACAGACAUGCUCUUUUUUUAAGUGCUUACAUUUUAAUAGAGAUGAAUCAGUUUUGGAAUCUAAGCUGUUUGCCAAGCUGAAGCUACAGGUUGUGAAAUAAUUUUUAACUUUUGGAAUCAUACUGCCUACUGUUACUCUAAAUAGAAAUAUAGGGUUUUUUUUAAUGUGAAUUUUUGCCUAUCUUUAAACAUUUCAAUGUCAGCCUUUGUUAACCUUAAAUACACUGAAUUGAAUCUACAAAAGUGAACCAUCUCAGACCUUUACUGAUACUACAACUUUUGUUUUCUGAUGGCCAAAAUACCAAAUGCCUGUUGUAUUUAUGGAUUAAAAACUGCUUAUAAAACCCUGUGUUACUACUCCUACUCUUGGAGAUGAUAAUAUUCUAUGUGGUCAAAUAUUUGGACUCAUUUAGGACUUAGAUAUUUCAGUGUACUUGAUUUUUUAAUUUAACUCUUUUUCACAGCCACGCUAAGGGUAAAAAGGAAUAAUUUCCUUCUGUCUUCCUUUUCAAGUAUUUCUGGGUAAGGGAUUCAAAAAACUAAAACUGUUUUUGUUUGUAAUAUAAAAUAUGGAAUUGAUCUUUCCAGGGUCAGAGAUGAUUAAUGUUUUUGCUAUAUACUUUUAUACAUUAUUUUCUUAUCAAACUAGUUAACAAGUAUUUUUAUAUGUUUGUAAGCAGAUAUGCUUUCAUAGCAUACCUUGUGUAUAUGUAAAGAUAAGUAUUUAAUUCUCACUGUUCACUUUUAACUGACAAAGAAAAACAAGUGGAAACUACAGAAACUGUGGUAGAACUUUUACUUGCUGGUCUGGUCUUGGUUGUACCCAUCUUUGGCCAGUCACAUAACUACUCAAGAAACCUUCCCAAUAGAGUACAACAGGAUGAGACUCUGAAAUCACUUUCAGUAUUCCCUGCUAGAUAUUGAUUGUUAUUUCAAGUAUUAAGUGUAAGCUUUUAAUGGAUAAUUAGUAUAACUGUGGAUGGCAUCUGAUUUUGUUUUUAAUUCUGUGGAUUGUGUUUAAGCAAUUCAAUAGUAUGUUCCUGAUUUUGAGAUGCUAAGUGGUAUUGCACAGUUGUCACUUUAUCAAGUGUGUACAACAGUCCCAUGAAGUUUAUAGAGCAUACCCUUGUAUAGCUUCAGGUGCUAGAAUUAAAAUUGAUCUGUUAUCACAA